CUUGCCGGCAUGGCUUCCGCGUCGGGGUGUGCGCCCCGGUUUCCCCCGGGGGGCGGCCAGGGCGUCCGGAGCUGCUGCUUGCAGCCAGCAGGCCCCGCCUCCUGGGCGACCCUUUUCUCGGCGUUCCCCCCAACACGCCUUCGGAGCAGGCUCUCGAAUCUUGAGCUCCCGGGAGCCUCAGAGUUCGGCCAGUGUUGCCGCUGCCCUCUCGAAGACGCGGACCUGUGGUCCCCAGCCUCUCCCAGGAGACCUGCGCCCUGUUCCUUUUCUCCCAGAGCCCCAAGUGGGGCGGGAAUGUGGGCAGUUAUGGGAGGCACGGAGGCUGCAGUUGGAGCUGGUCGGGGCUUUUUUAUCUGGCAGUUACUUCCUCAUCUGAGCUGGGCUCGGCCUGGCGGUCUCCAGAAAGGCCAGCUCUCGGCACUGUCUCGAGCUCUCCUCUCCUUUCCUUAACGCUUCUGGGUGACAGGAGCUGCAGUUGUGGCUGUUUUUGUUAAGUUUGAGAUCUUUCUUAGUGGCCGAACGGGGCUGCUGGGUAGUGCUUUUUGCUCCCAGCUCAGCUACUCCCCCAACCUUGGGAGAGGUUUUGUUUUGAAACUUUGUGUUUGGGCUUGGCCCUUUUUGAAUGCCUUGGUGUGUUUUGUGAUUAAAGUUGUUCAGUCAUACAACUUAACUAGCAUUCGGGAUCAUGAUGUGUUAUUCUCGUUAAUGUGGCGGUAAAAUAUAGUGUUUGAGUUUUGGCAAGCCACUUUAUUUCCUCAUUUUGAUAGGGGCCCUAGCUUCUCUGGUGAGAUAAGGCUAUGAAAAAUGGUGUGUGUGCGUGUUGGGGCAGGGGGUGGUCUUUUGGAAUGUAAUAGAUCAGCAAGCAGAAAGUAAAUUUUCUUGAUGAACUUGCUUUUGCAGAUAUAAACGGGAACGCAGUUUGUGAGAUUUGGAAGUAAUGUUGUAGGCUUCCGAUGUUCAUUUUUCUUCCUAUUGAUCAACGGUGUUAGACUGUCCUUUUUCACUAAUAUACAAGCUUUAUGGAUUUUUUUUGUGGAUGGCUUAGGCUUUGCUUCUGCUACUUGGGUUCAUUUGCUUUGAUUUUUCUUCAUGCUGUAUAAGAAACGUUACUAGGACAUUUAUAAGGCCUCAGUGGGGCAAAUUUGCAAAAAGAUACUAAAAAUUUAAGGGGAUGGAAUGAUGAUUAAGACUGGGAUUUGGAUCUCUAUUCCUCUGCGCUUUCUUUAAAAGAUGGCUGGGAUGGGAAAAGAAGUGUCCAUUUCAGAUUCAUUCUACCACCUUGGAGGCAAAACAUACUUAAGAUCCACUAUUAUAUGCAUACUUUGACCGAAGGCCUACUUUGCCCUAGCUAUUCAUUGGGAUUUUUUUCUGGUUCUUGCAGUGGUCGUCUCGUUUCCUCCAUCAGAUGAAUUGCUAAUGAGCUCUGCACCUGAAAUGGCUCCCCAUUCACUUUGUCGUUUGCUGUGCUCCCUAAGGGCAGAGGAUUUUGGAGCUCACUUCCUUGCUGGACACCCACUAAGCUAAAUACUGAAUAAUUUUACCACUGAUCCCACGGAACUGGGUUCUCAAACCAAGUAAAAAGUUGCAGUGAUUCUUGGAAAUUAAAGCAAAGAACAUUACAGCUGUGUUGAGGUCUUGCAUAGGGCUGUGUGAAUGUAGAAGCAAAGGCAGGUUUGUAUUUUGAGAAUACAUUUAUGCUUGUCUUACAUGUAUAUCCAGGGACAUAGAUGAGAAAACAGCCAGACCAAAACUCAGAGCCUUUAGAUUUUUUCACCAGCUUGCAAAAUUGUUCAAGAAUUGGUAUUUUGUUGAGGUUCUAUUAAUGACAAUGACCAGUGUAGGAUGAGAAUGGGCCGUUUUCUUUUUUUCUCAUUAAGAGAGAUUUCCUUUGGACCGUAGGCAUGUGGACCUUUCCAAUUUGCACCACACACGGUAGUAAACACAACUGUCUUCCAAUCAAAAGUGUUCUUCCCGUACUCAAGGGUGGAGUUUGCAAGCAGCUGGCCUGUGAUUGGGCAGAUUUUCAUUCAGUUAUGUUUAAGAUGUUUUCAGGCAUGCUUGGUUUUGAGUAAUGCCUAGCAGGGCGCCCCCUUUUAAGGAUGAGUAAUUGAGGGUUGGAUGAAUGAGUUUCUGAAGUGAUUGAAAACACACUUCUUAAUUUUAGAUUCCACGAAUACAUCUCUUUCUAAAUACUUUUUGAUUCAGAUAUCCUAUAAAAUACAGUACUGAUCCAUUAAAUGAAACCUUUUUUGGAAAACAGUAACAAAGCCAAGUGCUACCUUAAGAUCUUUGUAGAAUUUGAUGGCUGUAACUGGAAGCAACACUCCUGGGUAAAAGUUCAUGCUGAGGAAGUUAUCGUGCUUCUGCUGGAAGGGUCUCUUGUAUGGGCGCCCCGUGAGGACCCAGUCCUUCUCCAGGGCAUUCGAGUCUCCAUUGCACAAUGGCCAGCCCUGACUUUUACUCCCCUUGUAGAUAAACUGGGUUUGGGUUCUGUGGUUCCAGUGGAAUAUCUUCUGGAUCGAGAGCUUCGGUUCCUGUCAGAUGCCAAUGGGUUGCAUCUGUUUCAGAUGGGAACAGAUAGCCAAAACCAGAUUCUUUUGGAACAUGCUGCACUGAGAGAAACAGUUAAUGCUUUGAUCAGUGACCAAAAGCUACAAGAGAUAUUCAGCCGAGGUCCCUACAGUGUUCAAGGUCACAGGGUCAAAAUAUAUCAGCCAGAGGGGGAAGAAGGGUGGCUCUAUGGUGUUGUGAGCCAUCAGGACUCCAUCACUCGUCUUAUGGAGGUGUCUGUAACUGAGAGUGGUGAGAUCAAGUCGGUAGAUCCCAGACUAAUCCAUGUGAUGCUGAUGGAUAAUUCAGCGCCUCAAAGCGAGGGGGGUACGUUAAAAGCAGUAAAAUCUUCCAAAGGAAAGAAGAAGAGAGAAAGCAUAGAGGGGAAAGAUGGCCGGAGGAGGAAAAGUGCUUCGGACUCUGGGUGUGACCCUGCAUCAAAGAAAUUAAAAGGAGACAGGGGUGAAGUAGACAGUAAUGGGAGCGAUGGAGGUGAGGCAAGCCGAGGGCCCUGGAAAGGAGGGAAUGCCAGUGGAGAGCCAGGGCUGGAUCAGAGAGCCAAGCAGCCACCGUCUACAUUUGUCCCCCAGAUAAACCGCAACAUUCGCUUUGCCACUUACACCAAAGAAAACGGCAGGACUCUGGUGGUGCAGGAUGAGCCUGUAGGUGGGGACACACCUGCAUCUUUCACUCCAUAUUCUACAGCCACAGGUCAGACACCUUUGGCCCCAGAGGUGGGUGGAGCCGAAAACAAAGAGGCAGGAAAAACACUGGAACAAGUUGGCCAGGGCAUAGUGGCUUCCGCAGCUGUGGUCACUACCGCCAGCUCCACCCCAAACACAGUGAGGAUCUCAGACACUGGCCUUGCAGCAGGGACUGUGCCAGAAAAACAGAAAGGCAGCCGGUCGCAGGCCUCGGGAGAGAAUUCAAGAAAUUCUAUUCUGGCCUCUUCUGGAUUUGGAGCACCUCUCCCUAGUUCAUCGCAACCUUUGACUUUUGGAAGUGGAAGGAGCCAGUCCAAUGGUGUUCUAGCCACAGAGAACAAACCUUUGGGCUUCUCUUUUGGCUGUAGCUCUGCACAAGAGGCACAGAAAGACACUGAUCUCUCCAAAAACUUGUUUUUUCAAUGCAUGUCCCAAACUUUACCUACCAGUAACUACUUCACUACUGUUUCAGAGAGUUUGGCUGAUGAUUCUUCUAGUCGGGACUCAUUCAAACAAAGCCUUGAGAGCCUGAGCUCAGGCCUGUGUAAAGGCAGAUCCGUUCUUGGAACAGACACUAAGCCAGGCUCUAAGGCUGGCAGCUCUGUGGACCGGAAAGUGCCUGCAGAGUCCAUGCCCACCCUCACUCCAGCCUUCCCACGGAGCCUCCUAAAUGCCCGUACCCCAGAGAAUCAUGAAAAUCUAUUUUUACAGCCCCCCAAAUUGUCCCGAGAAGAGCCUUCUAAUCCUUUCCUGGCAUUUGUGGAGAAAGUUGAACACAGCCCUUUCAGUAGUUUUGCAUCUCAGGCAUCAGGUAGCUCCUCUUCUGCUACCACUGUCACCUCCAAGGUGGCACCCAGCUGGCCCGAGUCUCACUCCUCUGCAGAUUCGGCAUCUUUAGCAAAGAAGAAACCCCUCUUCAUUACAACUGACUCCUCCAAGCUAGUAUCUGGUGUUCUGGGCUCAGCUCUUACCAGUGGGGGCCCAAGCCUCUCUGCCAUGGGGAAUGGCCGCUCCAGCUCGCCCACCAGCAGCCUCACUCAGCCCAUUGAGAUGCCAACUCUCUCCUCUAGCCCCACAGAGGAGAGGCCAACUGUGGGGCCUGGGCAGCAGGACAAUCCCCUCCUCAAAACCUUUAGUAACGUCUUUGGCAGGCACUCAGGCGGCUUUCUGUCCUCCCCGGCAGAUUUUUCACAGGAGAACAAAGCUCCUUUUGAAGCUGUGAAAAGGUUCUCACUGGAUGAACGAAGCUUGGCUUGCAGACAAGACUCGGACUCCAGCACCAACAGUGACCUGUCAGAUUUGAGUGACUCUGAGGAGCAGCUGCAGGCUAAGACAGGCCUGAAGGGAAUUCCAGAGCACCUGAUGGGGAAGCUGGGCCCCAAUGGGGAGCGCAGUGCUGAGCUGUUGCUGGGCAAAAGCAAAGGGAAGCAGGCCCCCAAGGGCCGGCCUCGGACUGCCCCCCUGAAAGUUGGCCAGUCAGUGCUGAAAGAUGUAAGCAAAGUGAAGAAGCUGAAGCAAUCUGGAGAGCCCUUCCUGCAGGAUGGGUCAUGCAUCAAUGUGGCACCUCAUCUGCACAAGUGUCGUGAAUGCCGCCUGGAGCGGUACCGGAAGUUUAAGGAACAGGAGCAAGAUGAUUCUACUGUAGCCUGCCGUUUCUUUCACUUCCGGAGGUUGAUCUUCACUCGAAAAGGGGUACUCCGUGUGGAGGGGUUUUUAAGCCCCCAGCAAAGUGACCCUGAUGCCAUGAACCUGUGGAUUCCCUCUUCCUCCCUAGCAGAAGGGAUAGAUCUAGAGACCUCAAAAUACAUCCUGGCCAAUGUUGGGGACCAGUUCUGCCAGCUCGUAAUGUCUGAGAAGGAGGCCAUGAUGAUGGUGGAGCCACACCAGAAAGUGGCAUGGAAGCGAGCUGUGCGUGGUGUACGGGAGAUGUGUGAUGUGUGUGAAACAACUCUCUUCAACAUCCACUGGGUUUGUCGCAAAUGUGGAUUUGGGGUCUGCCUUGACUGUUACCGGCUCAGGAAAAGCCGGCCACGCAGUGAGACAGAAGAGAUGGGUGAUGAAGAAGUUUUCUCCUGGUUGAAGUGUGCAAAGGGACAGUCCCACGAACCAGAGAAUCUCAUGCCCACACAAAUUAUUCCUGGCACAGCUCUUUACAAUAUUGGAGACAUGGUACAUGCUGCCCGGGGCAAGUGGGGAAUUAAAGCAAACUGCCCUUGUAUCAGUCGACAGAACAAAUCUGUAUUGAGACCUGCCGUCACCAAUGGGAUGUCACAGCUUCCUAGCAUAAACCCUAGUGCCUCUUCUGGAAACGAAACUACCUUCUCUGGUGGAGGAGGACCGGCACCAGUAACAACUCCAGAGCCGGACCAUGUUCCCAAAGCCGACAGCACUGACAUCAGAUCUGAAGAGCCUCUGAAAACAGACAGUUCGGCAUCAAAUAGCAAUAGUGAACUGAAAGCCAUCAGGCCUCCUUGCCCUGACACGGCCCCACCCUCCUCCGCCCUGCACUGGUUGGCAGAUUUAGCAACUCAGAAGGCUAAAGAAGAAACAAAAGAAGCAGGGUCCCUGAGGUCGGUGCUCAAUAAAGAGUCUCAUUCACCCUUUGGGCUGGACUCGUUCAACUCCACUGCAAAGGUCUCUCCGCUGACUCCAAAGCUUUUUAACAGUCUGUUGCUGGGUCCCACUGCCUCCAACAACAAAACCGAAGGGUCUAGCCUUCGAGACCUCCUUCACUCCGGGCCGGGAAAACUUCCUCAAACCCCCUUGGACACAGGCAUACCCUUUCCCCCGGUCUUCUCUACAUCCUCAGCAGGAGUGAAGAGCAAGGCCAGCCUACCCAACUUUCUUGACCACAUCAUUGCCUCAGUGGUAGAAAAUAAGAAAACCUCAGAUGCUUCAAAGCGGGCCUGCAACUUGACUGAUACCCAGAAGGAAGUGAAGGAGAUGGUGAUGGGGUUAAAUGUGCUAGAUCCCCAUACUUCUCACUCCUGGCUUUGUGAUGGGAGGCUUCUGUGUCUCCAUGACCCCAGCAACAAAAACAAUUGGAAGAUCUUCCGGGAGUGUUGGAAGCAAGGUCAGCCAGUGCUGGUUUCGGGGGUACAUAAAAAGCUCAAGUCUGAGCUCUGGAAGCCAGAAGCCUUUAGCCAGGAAUUUGGAGACCAGGAUGUAGACUUGGUGAACUGCAGGAACUGUGCUAUAAUUUCCGAUGUGAAAGUUCGGGAUUUCUGGGAUGGUUUCGAGAUCAUAUGCAAACGACUACGGUCAGAAGAUGGGCAGCCAAUGGUGCUCAAACUCAAGGACUGGCCUCCUGGGGAAGAUUUUCGAGACAUGAUGCCAACCAGGUUUGAAGAUCUGAUGGAGAACCUUCCUCUGCCAGAAUAUACCAAACGAGAUGGCAGGCUCAAUCUGGCCUCUAGGCUACCUAGCUACUUUGUAAGGCCUGAUCUGGGCCCCAAGAUGUACAACGCCUAUGGGUUGAUAACAGCAGAAGAUAGAAGAGUUGGUACAACAAAUCUUCACUUAGAUGUGUCUGAUGCUGUUAAUGUGAUGGUGUAUGUUGGGAUUCCCAUCGGGGAGGGUGCUCAUGAUGAAGAGGUACUCAAGACAAUUGACGAGGGAGAUGCCGAUGAGGUGACGAAGCAGAGGAUUCAUGAUGGAAAAGAGAAGCCAGGUGCUUUAUGGCACAUCUAUGCAGCCAAGGAUGCAGAGAAGAUCCGGGAGCUGCUCCGAAAGGUUGGAGAAGAACAAGGCCAAGAGAACCCCCCUGAUCAUGACCCAAUUCAUGACCAAAGUUGGUACCUGGACCAGACCCUCCGUAAGCGACUCUAUGAGGAGUAUGGCGUGCAAGGCUGGGCUAUUGUGCAGUUCCUAGGUGAUGCUGUUUUCAUACCUGCUGGAGCCCCACACCAGGUUCACAAUCUAUACAGUUGCAUAAAAGUAGCAGAAGACUUUGUAUCUCCAGAACAUGUAAAGCACUGUUUCCGCCUGACUCAGGAAUUCAGGCAUCUCUCUAACACUCAUACAAAUCAUGAGGAUAAACUGCAGGUGAAGAACAUCAUUUACCAUGCAGUGAAAGAUGCGGUUGGCACCCUCAAGGCUCAUGAAUCCAAACUGGCAAGGUCCUAGGCAUGGAGAAACUCCAAGCUCCUCUGUGAAGCAGGUCUUUCACUCACAACACUUAACAGGGAACGGCAGGGCUCUUUGCUGGAGCAGAGGCCCUUCACCCAGAGCCAGUGUGGUCAGUAUUCCAAACUCUCCAGCCACUCUCUUCUACGCUGCCUCAACACUGAAGGUUGACACAGGAAAGUCGUACUGUUCACACACACAGUUUGAGACUCCAAGCCAAGAGUGCCACAUCCCUAUCCUGUGGCCUUUUGGAAAUCCAAAUUGCCUGAACAUGGCGGGGCUUUCCUGCACAUUCUCCUGAUUUGAGAUUCACGGGCACACCUUUCUUUUCUUUUCCUCUUGUGCCUAGUUAAGUGGAAAUGUGUUUGGAGAUAGGGGAAAUCACAUAACUGGUACAAGUAUGGGGUAAUUGCUUAAACAUGCCUGGUGGAAGUCUGAUAGCGUCUCUGCACGUGACCUCUGACAAAGCCCAUCCCAGGAGACGGGGUGAAGCUAUUCCCCACACUCUCCUGUGAACACUGGAGUCUUGCAAGACCCAGGGAGAACCCACUGCUUUUCCCAGGAGGCUCCAGGAUUAGGAAAUGUGUGUAUUUAGUGAAAAAUAGGUUUGUAGUGAAAUAGUUACUAUUUCAUGAAAGUAGAUAUUUUUAGAAUUUUUGAAAUACCACAGUUGUUUUCCUGGAUUAUAAGGAAAGGCACAUUACAUUUAGUCUUCCUUUCGAUAUAAAACUCUUUGAAGAAAUAUGAUUUUUAGAAAUCAGCUACCCAUUAUAGCACAAAAUCAGCCAAAGCAGAAUUUUUAAAAAUUGGCUUUUUUAGGAUUCUUUUUCUCCCCCUCCCAUCUUAGUCUUACCUUGAGGGAACAGUCAUAUGAGAAGGAACUUUGUCACAUCUAAGCUGUGGUGUGUUCCCCAUGUGUGUGUACAACACUGGUGACUCCAGGAACCAUUUUCACCUAUUACCAGUGUUCCCUGGGGACUCCUCUUAAUGUUUCCAAAUGGGAAGGACAGUUGAUUUCCAACAUGAGGUUUUUUGUUUUUUAUCCAGAAAUAUUUUCAGCAAAACUUUCCAACUGAGUGGAGUCUGAUUAAGGAUUUAUUUGAAAAUGGUGGGAUUCAUUGGCCCAUAGGUACAUUGGAAAAUGUAUAUCUCUCCAGCUGUACUGUAGUGCCCUGCAGGCUGUUUAUAUGUUCACAGUUACUUUUUUUUUUUUUUUUAAAUAAAAGUCAUUUAAUGUAGAAUACUUUUAAUUUCACUUUCUGUAUUUUAAUUUUGUUGAAGGGCUGAUUGGGAUUUCCAUGUUCUUAUUAAAAAUCUAACAAAUCUG